ACGGCUUACCCGGGCUCCGACAGCGGCUGCAGGUCUCCAAGUUGCGGCCGCUGGAGCCCGAGCCAUGCGGACCGCGGACCGGGAGGCGCGCCCGGGGCUUCCGUCCCUGCUGCUGCUGCUGCUGGCCGGGGCCGGGCUGUCAGCCGCCUCGCCCCCAGCAGCGCCGCGCUUCAACGUGAGCCUGGACUCGGUCCCCGAGCUGCGCUGGCUGCCCGUGCUGCGGCACUACGACUUGGACUUGGUGCGCGCCGCGAUGGCGCAAGUCAUCGGGGACAGAGUCCCCAAGUGGGUGCACGUGUUAAUCGGAAAAGUGGUCCUGGAGCUGGAGCGCUUCCUGCCCCAGCCCUUCACCGGCGAGAUCCGCGGCAUGUGUGACUUCAUGAACCUCAGCCUGGCGGACUGCCUUCUGGUCAACCUGGCCUACGAGUCCUCCGUGUUCUGCACCAGUAUUGUGGCUCAAGACUCCAGAGGCCACAUUUACCAUGGUCGGAAUUUGGAUUAUCCUUUUGGGAAUGUCUUACGCAAGCUGACAGUGGAUGUGCAAUUCUUAAAGAAUGGGCAGAUUGCAUUCACAGGAACUACUUUUAUUGGCUAUGUAGGAUUAUGGACUGGCCAGAGCCCACACAAGUUUACAGUUUCUGGUGAUGAACGAGAUAAAGGCUGGUGGUGGGAGAAUGCUAUCGCUGCCCUGUUUCGGAGACACAUUCCCGUCAGCUGGCUGAUCCGCGCUACCCUGAGUGAGUCGGAAAACUUCGAAGCAGCUGUUGGCAAGUUGGCCAAGACUCCCCUUAUUGCUGAUGUUUAUUACAUUGUUGGUGGCACGUCCCCCCGGGAGGGGGUGGUCAUCACGAGGAACAGAGAUGGCCCAGCAGACAUUUGGCCUCUAGAUCCUUUGAAUGGAGCGUGGUUCCGAGUUGAGACAAAUUACGACCACUGGAAGCCAGCACCCAAGGAAGAUGACCGGAGAACAUCUGCCAUCAAGGCCCUUAAUGCUACAGGACAAGCAAACCUCAGCCUGGAGGCACUUUUCCAGAUUUUGUCGGUGGUUCCAGUUUAUAACAAUGAAAGCAGGCCAGGUGCGGUGGCUCACGCCUGUAAUCCCAGCCCUUUGGGAGGCCAAGGCGGGUGGAUCACUUGAGGUCAGGAGUUCAAGACCAGCCUGGCCAACAUGGUGAAACCUCGUCUCUACUAAAAAUACAAAAAUCAACCAGGCAUGACGGUGCACGCCUGUUAUCACAGCUACUUGGGAAGCAGCGGCUGGAGAAUUGCUUGAACCUGGGAAGUCGAGGCUGCAAGUGAGCUGAGAUCAUGCCAUGGCAGUCUAGCCUGGGCAACAGAGCGAGACUCUGUUUCAAAAAAAAAAAGAAAAGAAAACUAAUUAGUCAGUAUUCUGCUACUCAAACAAAUGAGCUAUUUGGAUAACAAAGCAUACCCAGUGGUCUGCUAGUAAACCAGCUCUUUGUGUGGGAAGGGACAAAUGAAAAAAUUCCCAAAUUUGUAGCAUUUGUUGACUUCCAUGGUGUGAAUACUCCCACAUGGCUGAUUUCAGGCUUAUAGUUGGCUCAUACACUUCCUGCAUAUUUAAUAAUUGGCCCUCACCAGACUGUAGGAGCUAGCUCCAAUGCACUAUUGACUGUACCCUUCAUAGCGGGGCACAAUGUUGCCCUUUUAAUAGUCAUUUUUUAAAUGGGGGUUAAUAAACUACUUUUGUGUUCUUAUAGUUUUUUUAGGUAAUUAUAGAAGUGAUGAAUAUAUCUGGCUGGGCGCAGUGGCUCACAUCUGUAAUCCUAGUACUUUGGAAGCCGAGGCGGGUGGAUCACUUGAGGUCAGGAGUUCGAGACCAGCCUGGCCAACAUGGUGAAACCUCAUCUCUACUAAAAAUACAAAAAUUAGCCAGGCGUCAUGGUGCGUGCCUGUAAUCCCAGCUACUUGGGAGGUGGAGGCAGGAAAAUCACUCGAAUCCGGGAGACAGAGGUUGCAGUGAGCUGAGAUUGCACUCCAGCCUGGGCGACAGAGGGAGACUCCGUCUUAAAAAAAAAAAAAAAAAAAAAAAAAAAGAAGUGAUGAAUAUAUCUUUUAAAAAUUAGUAUUAUAAUAAAAUAGUUACAUUUAUUUUAAUAAAACAAAGCAUUUUCUCUGCUUUGAACAGCCCUCAUAAUUUUACAUGGUGGCAGUGGCCAGUUGGCUGUAUUAUAAUUGAGUUAAGCAUUCUCCAGUUGUUAGAUUUUCCUCUAUUAAAACUCUGAAAUAAACAUAUUCGUUUGCCUCUCCCCUGCUUACUUUCAGAUUAUUUCCCUUGGCUGAAUUCCCAGAAGUAGGAUUACUGAGUUAACAGUUAUGAAUGUUUAAAUGGUUUCUGAAAUGGUUUGGUCAAAAUAAAAUUGUUAGAAAUUAUAAA